AGUGACGUCGUGGGCUGCAGCGCAGCAGCACCCAACGCAGUGAGUACCUUGAUCUCCUGCGUGGCCUCGUCCCUGGUCUUAGUUCCACCGGGCAGCGGGAGUCAGGACCGCCUGUCCUCAGACCCCUCCGCAGCGACUGUGGCGGCCGCAGUCUAGCAGGAAAGGAGAGGGAGCUUUCCCCGAAGACCCUCCUGGACCAGCCCCAGGCUCCUGUGCUGGUGAGGCCGAGGGAGAGGGAUGUGGGCAUAGGACACGUAGCAGGAUUUCCAUUUUAGAGGCAGCCGGACCUGUCUUCAGGUCCCUUCCUUGGUGAGAGACAGGGGUACGCCAGAGGAAGCUGGGCGCUCGGCCUCUGUGCAGCCUCAUCUCCUGGAAUCUGAGUAUUGAAAACUGGGCUUUUACUUCGCACACCUCAGCACAGACUCCCAUGGGAAUCCAGGUCACAGCAAAGCAGCCCUGGGCCUCCAUUCUCCUUUAAGCAAGCAUGACAAUCCUCACUUCACUGAGUUUUUAUUAAAACUAGCAAUGACCUUAGAAAGCAAGGCAUGACCUCAGCUCCACUUUUGAGGCUGCAGUCCAUUCAGAGAGGUUUCGCAGACUCGGUAACGGCCAGAACAGACAGCCUGGGCCCUGCCGCAGGCUGACUCAGAAUCUUUGGGAGUAGUGACCAACUUCUGCUUUUGGAAAAACCUCUACAGGCGGUUCUGAGAAGUCCAAGGGUUGCUGGGAGAGGUUGGUUGCACGCCAGGGCCUGUACUGACCACCUCCACGUGCCACUGGGGCUGUAAGGAGGAAUGGCGGCCGUGGGCAGCCUGCUUGGCCGGCUGAGGCAGAGCACCGUGAAGGCCACCGGACCUGCACUCCGCCGCCUGCACACAUCCUCCUGGCGAGCUGACAGCAGCAGGGCCUCACUCACUCGUGUGCACCGCCAGGCUUAUGCACGACUCUACCCCGUGCUGCUGGUGAAGCAGGAUGGCUCCACCAUCCACAUCCGCUACAGGGAGCCACGGCGCAUGCUGGCGAUGCCCAUAGAUCUGGACACCCUGUCUCCUGAGGAGCGCCGGGCCAGGCUGCGGAAGCGUGAGGCUCAGCUCCAGUCGAGGAAGGAGUACGAGCAGGAGCUCAGUGAUGACUUGCAUGUGGAGCGCUACCGACAGUUCUGGACCAGGACCAAGAAGUGACCGUGGCUCCAGCCACCCCGGGACAUUGCUAAGAUGGGAGGGCUGUUCUUAAAUCACUCGUUCUUGAAGCUGCCA